ACCACGCCCCCAUCUCCGUCCGUGUACACACACUCACACAAGGACGCCAACCCCACCUAGAUGCAAAGCAGGAUUCAAAAGAACAUCUUUGCGUUUUCUACCGGCUCCCCAUCAUCGUACUAGGGAGGAAGAAGCGGGUGAGAAACAAAACUUCUUUCCAUUGUCCUGCCCGUUUCUGCGGACUUGUUCUGAGGCCGAGGAGCCUGUGUUGGAAGAGAUGGUGAUGGGCCUGGGCGUUUUGUUGUUGGUCUUCGUGCUGGGUCUGGGUCUGACCCCACCGACCCUGGCUCAGGAUAACUCCAGGCACCUCUAAGAUACUGAUGGCUCUGCAGAGGACCCAUUCAUUGCUUCUGCUUUUGCUGCUGACCCUGCUGGGGCUGGGGCUGGUCCAGCCCUCCUAUGGCCAGGAUGGCAUGUACCAGCGAUUCCUGCGGCAACACGUGCACCCUGAGGAGACAGGUGGCAGUGAUCGCUACUGCAACUUGAUGAUGCAAAGACGGAAGAUGACUUUGUAUCACUGCAAGCGCUUCAACACCUUCAUCCAUGAAGAUAUCUGGAACAUUCGUAGUAUCUGCAGCACCACCAAUAUCCAAUGCAAGAACGGCAAGAUGAACUGCCAUGAGGGUGUAGUGAAGGUCACAGAUUGCAGGGACACAGGAAGUUCCAGGGCACCCAACUGCAGAUAUCGGGCCAUAGCGAGCACUAGACGUGUUGUCAUUGCCUGUGAGGGUAACCCACAGGUGCCUGUGCACUUUGACGGUUAGAUGCCACCAUGUAGGGAUUAUCGCGAGUGGUUGACCUUACACUUACUCCUUAAAUAGCAGUGAGUAAUGCAUUUGAGCUGUCCCAGGCUCUGUCUCCUCAGCUCAUUUCCUACUCUUUUUCUCUAUAUAACUCAUUCUAUUAAAUACAUUGCACCAAAGAGAUAUGGAGACAUAAACCUGUAAUGAAUGAGGCUGGGCUUUUCUGUAAUAAGCUUCCUUUUAUAAUACUGGUCAGCUUAGCUCUCUCAGAUCCUAUCCUGUGGAAUUUAGUUAUUAUGUGUAUUUAUGUAGUAUUUCAAACAUUUCAAAAUGCUUUCAUCUAUGUUUAUCACAUUUUAAUACCACAGCACUUAUAAUGAUGUCACUACAUAUAGAAGCUCAAAGUUAAGGGAUUUGCUGAAGACUGUAAAGUUAAUGGAAGAAUUGAGACAAAAAUCCAGUGUAGCUGGCCACUUAUCCAGGGCUUUUUCUACUUCAUCACAAGGAAUGUUUUGAAAGUGUCUGCUUUUUUUAUCCUUAAAAUUCACCUGUCAGGGAGGCAUUAAAAAUUUGGAAAUGUAUGCCAGCAAAAUGUGAGCUCUGUAUUUUUUGGCAUUCUUAUGUUUGGGUUUAAUAAGAUUAAGAAAAUGAUACUGGGAAUUUUCUUUUUCCUGAAACUUUGAAUCACCCUAGUAAGUCAAAGUACUAAAAAAUGUACUAGAUCAUUAAGACUUAUGUGCUCUUACUGAUUGAAAGAUUUUUUAUGUUUUCCUUGUAAUAAAGGACCUAAACCGAAGGUACCUGAGAAGACUGUGCUAUGGUAUUAUUUUUUUUCUCUGACUUUUAAAUUCUUGUUUAGUUUAUAAACAUGCAUGCACCUUAAUAACCUCAUAAACUCUGGUCAAAGACUAAUGCCUAUCAGAUCCAUGACCACAACACAGAAGAUUUGUCUCAUUUACUCCAGAGAGAAUGAUUCCUCUCAAAGACAAUUCUCACAGCUCUUCCUUCUCCCUUAGAAUAUUUAGAAGCAAAUUAGGGAGCUGUCAGGUCUCUGAGCCCAAGCCUGCACGUAUACAUCCAGAUGGCCUGAAGCAACUGAAGAACCACAAAAGAAGUGAAAAUAACCAAUUCCUGCCUUAACUGAUGACAUUCCACCACUGUGAUUUGUUCCUGCCCCACCUUAACUGAUCAAUUAGCCUUGUGACAUUCCUUCUCCUGGACAAUUAGACUCAGGAGCUCCCCACCAGAGCACCUUGUGACCCCCGCCCCUGCCCGCUAGAGAAUAACCCACUUUGACCGUAAUUUCCCACUACCAACCCAAAUCCUAUAAAACUGCCCCACCCCAUCUCCCUUUGCUGACUCCUUUUUUGGACUCAGUCUGCCUGCACCCAGGUGAUUAAAAAGCUUUAUUGCUCACACAAA